AGAACGCCACCGACUUGAGGAAGCCCAGUACAUUUCAAGUUGGUCGCGGCUUGGGCUCCGCUUUGGGGAGGGGCAGCAGGUUUAUUCACUGGAUCUCUGAAUACCCAGGCCCCCUCCACCAUGGCCAGCCGGGGUGGGGGCCGGGGUCGUGGCCGGGGCCAGUUGACCUUCAACGUGGAGGCCGUGGGCAUUGGGAAAGGGGAUGCUUUGCCCCCACCCACCCUGCAGCCUUCUCCACUCUUCCCUCCCUUGGAGUUCCGCCCAGUACCUUUGCCCUCAGGCGAGGAAGGGGAAUAUGUCCUGGCACUGAAGCAAGAGCUACGAGGAGCCAUGAGGCAGCUCCCCUACUUCAUCCGGCCAGCUGUCCCCAAGAGAGAUGUGGAGCGUUAUUCAGACAAAUAUCAGAUGUCAGGUCCGAUUGACAAUGCCAUCGAUUGGAACCCUGAUUGGCGGCGUCUACCCCGGGAGCUAAAGAUCCGAGUGCGGAAGCUACAGAAGGAACGGAUUACAAUUCUGCUCCCCAAGAGGCCCCCUAAGACCACAGAAGAUAAGGAGGAAACAAUACAGAAACUAGAGACCCUGGAGAAGAAGGAAGAAGAAGUAACUUCAGAGGAGGAUGAGGAGAAAGAAGAAGAAGAAGAGAAGGAAGAGGAGGAAGAAGAAGAGUAUGAUGAAGAAGAACAUGAAGAGGAAACUGAUUACAUCAUGUCAUAUUUUGACAAUGGAGAGGACUUUGGUGGUGACAGUGAUGACAAUAUGGACGAGGCUAUAUACUGAAGAAGGACUCUGGACCCUCGUGUCUUUCUUUAGGAUACAGAGAGUAACUGUACCUAUUAUUUGUUUCUUCAGACAAGCAAAUCAUUUGGUCAGAGUUCAUAUAAUCUGUCUGUUCCCUGGAGAUGGGAAUAGAGGAUGAUGACAGUUUAUUUUCUACACUUCCCCUCCUUCCACAUUUGUAUCACCUUUGCUAUCUUGGGGAAAGUGCAAAGGACAAACAUCUCAAUUGUAUGAAGGGAGAAAGGAGAAUUGAAAGAAGAACUGGGGUUGUUAGAGCUGAGAUGACUGUACACAUACCCCUGCCCAAUUUAUAUAGCUCUUUGUGGAGAUAAUUAGGGGUGGGAGCAGUUUGAAGGAGUAAGCCUGGUUUUAUACUUUUAAAUAAAGUGUUUUUAUCUGUC